CCCUAACCGAGGCAGCAGCGGACGUGAGCGAUAAUGGCGGAUAUGGAGGAUCUCUUCGGGAGCGACGCCGACAGCGAAGCUGAGCGUAAAGAUUCUGAUUCUGGAUCUGACUCAGAUUCUGAUCAAGAGAAUGCUGCCUCUGGCAGUAAUGCCUCUGGAAGUGAAAGUGAUCAGGAUGAAAGAGGUGAUUCAGGACAACCAAGUAAUAAGGAACUGUUUGGAGAUGACAGUGAGGACGAGGGAGCUUCACAUCAUAGUGGUAGUGAUAAUCACUCUGAAAGAUCAGACAAUAGAUCAGAAGCUUCUGAGCGUUCUGACCAUGAGGACAAUGACCCCUCAGAUGUAGAUCAGCACAGUGGAUCAGAAGCCCCUAAUGAUGAUGAAGACGAAGGUCAUAGAUCGGAUGGAGGGAGCCAUCAUUCAGAAGCAGAAGGUUCUGAAAAAGCACAUUCAGAUGAUGAAAAAUGGGGCAGAGAAGAUAAAAGUGACCAGUCAGAUGAUGAAAAGAUACAAAAUUCUGAUGAUGAGGAGAGGGCACAAGGAUCUGAUGAAGAUAAGCUGCAGAAUUCUGACGAUGAUGAGAAAAUGCAGAACACAGAUGAUGAGGAGAGGCCUCAGCUUUCCGAUGAUGAGAGACAACAGCUAUCUGAGGAGGAAAAGGCUAAUUCUGAUGAUGAACGGCCGGUAGCUUCUGAUAAUGAUGAUGAGAAACAGAAUUCUGAUGAUGAAGAACAACCACAGCUGUCUGAUGAAGAGAAAAUGCAAAAUUCUGAUGAUGAAAGGCCACAGGCCUCAGAUGAAGAACACAGGCAUUCAGAUGAUGAAGAGGAACAGGAUCAUAAAUCAGAAUCUGCAAGAGGCAGUGAUAGUGAAGAUGAAGUUUUACGAAUGAAACGCAAGAAUGCGAUUGCAUCUGAUUCAGAAGCGGAUAGUGACACUGAGGUGCCAAAAGAUAAUAGUGGAACCAUGGAUUUAUUUGGAGGUGCAGAUGAUAUCUCUUCAGGGAGUGAUGGAGAAGACAAACCACCUACUCCAGGACAGCCUGUUGAUGAAAAUGGAUUGCCUCAGGAUCAACAGGAAGAGGAGCCAAUUCCUGAGACCAGAAUAGAAGUAGAAAUACCCAAAGUAAACACUGAUUUAGGAAACGACUUAUAUUUUGUUAAACUGCCCAACUUUCUCAGUGUAGAGCCCAGACCUUUUGAUCCUCAGUAUUAUGAAGAUGAAUUUGAAGAUGAAGAAAUGCUGGAUGAAGAAGGUAGAACCAGGUUAAAAUUAAAGGUAGAAAAUACUAUAAGAUGGAGGAUACGCCGAGAUGAAGAAGGAAAUGAAAUUAAAGAAAGCAAUGCUCGGAUAGUCAAGUGGUCAGAUGGAAGCAUGUCCCUGCAUUUAGGCAAUGAAGUGUUUGAUGUGUACAAAGCCCCACUGCAGGGCGACCACAAUCAUCUUUUUAUAAGACAAGGUACUGGUCUACAGGGACAAGCAGUCUUUAAAACGAAACUCACCUUCAGACCUCACUCUACGGACAGUGCCACACAUAGAAAGAUGACUCUGUCACUUGCAGAUAGGUGUUCAAAGACACAGAAGAUUAGAAUCUUGCCAAUGGCUGGUCGUGAUCCUGAAUGCCAACGCACAGAAAUGAUUAAGAAAGAAGAAGAACGUUUGAGGGCUUCCAUACGUAGGGAAUCUCAGCAGCGCCGAAUGAGAGAGAAACAGCACCAGCGGGGGCUGAGCGCCAGUUACCUGGAACCUGAUCGAUACGAUGAGGAGGAGGAAGGCGAGGAGUCCAUCAGCUUGGCUGCCAUUAAAAACCGAUAUAAAGGGGGCAUUCGAGAGGAACGAGCCAGAAUCUAUUCAUCAGACAGUGAUGAGGGAUCAGAAGAAGAUAAAGCUCAAAGAUUACUCAAAGCAAAGAAACUUACCAGUGAUGAGGAGUCUGGGAAAAGGGAAAGACCCAAGCUGAAAGAAACAUGGAGACAGUGGAAAGGAGAGGUAUCAAGGCCAACCCUCAGCUUUCUUAGACAAAACAGGAAGGUGAACCUUCCGGAAAGAGAAAAGCAGAAGAUGAUGAUAAAGCAAAUAAAAAGCAUAAGAAGUAUGUGAUCAGCGAUGAAGAGGAAGAAGAUGAUGAUUGAAGUAUGAAAUAUGAAAACAUUUUAUAUAUUUUAUUGUACAGUUAUAAAUAUGUAAACAUGAGUUAUUUUGAUUGAAAUGAAUCGAUUUGCUUUUGUGUAAUUUUAAUUGUAAUAAAACAAUUUAAAAGCAA